GAGCGGCGGGCCGAGGGAGGGCGCAGCAGCUGCUCCCUGAACACUUUCUGACCCAACAGUCCCCCAGCGCCGGACGCGCCGCGCCCUGGCGGCUCUAGGGACCCCCCCCGCGCCUGCACUUAGCCCCGCGCCCGAGGUGAGCCCGGCCCCUAAAUCCUCCGGGCGGGGGUGGGGGUGCGGGACGCUCCUUUUUUGUUGGGGGUCUUGGAGGCGCGAAGGCACUAGGCGCCUCGGCAGAUGGCUGCACCCCUCGCUUGCGGCUCCCCGUGUCUUUUGGGGGGCCGGGUGCGGGCGCGGAAUCCGGGAGGUGUCCGCACAAAAGGCCGAGAAAACUGCGCGAGGCCUCCCUCCCUCCGCCCUCCCCGCCCCCUCCCCUCCGCGCCCGCUCCUCCUCUUUCAAACCCGGCCGGCCCGAGUGGAGUCAGCUCAGUCCCGGCAGCCGCCGCGCGAGGAAAUGGCCGAGGGGCCGGAGCCACAGUCCACAGACAAACGAAUUUAAAGGAGCAACCGAGGAGGCACCUGCGAAAGAAAGCCCACACACAGGUGAAUUUAAAGGAGCAGCCCUGGUGUCACCUAUCAGUAAAAGACUAUUUGGAGUUUUCCUCGUCUUACUGGAUGUCACUCUCGUCCUUGCCGACCUAAUUUUCACUGACAGCAAACUUUAUAUUCCUUUGGAGUAUCGUUCUAUUUCUCUAGCUAUUGCCUUAUUUUUUCUCAUGGAUGUUCUUCUUCGAGUAUUUGUAGAAGGGUGUUGGAGCGGGCCGGAGAGAAGUAGAGUGGGCUGCGAGGAGAAGGAAACAGGCCUUUCGGAGGCUCCUCAUCCCUCGGAGGUCAUCCCUUACUCCAGCAAGAGUGAGCCAUGGAGCUACGUGUGGGGAACAAGUACCGCCUGGGACGGAAGAUCGGGAGCGGGUCCUUCGGAGAUAUCUACCUGGGUGCCAACAUCGCCUCUGGUGAGGAAGUCGCCAUCAAGCUGGAGUGUGUGAAGACAAAGCACCCCCAGCUGCACAUCGAGAGCAAGUUCUACAAGAUGAUGCAGGGUGGCGUGGGGAUCCCGUCCAUCAAGUGGUGCGGAGCUGAGGGCGACUACAACGUGAUGGUCAUGGAGCUGCUGGGGCCUAGCCUCGAGGACCUGUUCAACUUCUGUUCCCGCAAAUUCAGCCUCAAGACGGUGCUGCUCUUGGCCGACCAGAUGAUCAGCCGCAUCGAGUAUAUCCACUCCAAGAACUUCAUCCACCGGGACGUCAAGCCCGACAACUUCCUCAUGGGGCUGGGGAAGAAGGGCAACCUGGUCUACAUCAUCGACUUCGGCCUGGCCAAGAAGUACCGGGACGCCCGCACCCACCAGCACAUUCCCUACCGGGAAAACAAGAACCUGACCGGCACGGCCCGCUACGCUUCCAUCAACACGCACCUGGGCAUUGAGCAAAGCCGUCGAGAUGACCUGGAGAGCCUGGGCUACGUGCUCAUGUACUUCAACCUGGGCUCCCUGCCCUGGCAGGGGCUCAAAGCAGCCACCAAGCGCCAGAAGUAUGAACGGAUCAGCGAGAAGAAGAUGUCAACGCCCAUCGAGGUCCUCUGCAAAGGCUAUCCCUCCGAAUUCUCAACAUACCUCAACUUCUGCCGCUCCCUGCGGUUUGACGACAAGCCCGACUACUCUUACCUACGUCAGCUCUUCCGCAACCUCUUCCACCGGCAGGGCUUCUCCUAUGACUACGUCUUUGACUGGAACAUGCUGAAAUUCGGUGCAGCCCGGAAUCCCGAGGAUGUGGACCGGGAGCGGCGAGAACACGAACGCGAGGAGAGGAUGGGGCAGCUACGGGGGUCCGCGACCCGAGCCCUGCCCCCUGGCCCACCCACGGGGGCCACUGCCAACCGGCUCCGCAGUGCCGCCGAGCCCGUGGCUUCCACGCCAGCCUCCCGCAUCCAGCCGGCUGGCAAUACUUCUCCCAGAGCGAUCUCGCGGGUCGACCGGGAGAGGAAGGUGAGUAUGAGGCUGCACAGGGGUGCGCCCGCCAACGUCUCCUCCUCAGACCUCACUGGGCGGCAAGAGGUCUCCCGGAUCCCAGCCUCACAGACAAGUGUGCCAUUUGACCAUCUCGGGAAGUGAGGAGAGCCCCCAUUGGACCAGUGUUUGCUUAGUGUCUUCACUGUAUUUUCUUUAAAAAAAAAAAAAAAAAAAAAAAGGCAAAAAUAAACCACUCAAAAGAACAACAAAAAAACCCAGCACAAAACCGACGAUGGAGUUUGUUUCUUUGAUUUCUUUGCCAAUGGCAAGAAGAUGAGAUGCCCUCAGCACUGAGGAUUCUUGCCCCCUUGUGGUGCCCGCUGCCCCCAACCUUCAGGCUGCCAGAUGCUCCCCUGACAACACCAGGCUACAGGAGCCAGACGCCAGGGCCUGCCCGGCCUCCUGUUCCUGCCCCCACCCACCACCUGCCUGGAGAGGAACGGGUCGGGUCCGUGUCGGAGAAGUGACAGGUCCCAGAGCCAAAGCCGGCCCUCAAGCAUCAUCAGGGAGUGGUGUAGUCAGUUGAAGGCAGUUCCCACCGAGUUUUCCGAGCCUCAGAAUCCAGGAGAUACGCACAGCCCCACCCACUCUGAGAUGACAGUGGCUGACUUCCCGUGCUGGGCUUUUCCAUUGUCCCCCUGGCCUCCAGGCUCCUCCUCUGCCUCUCCAUGGAGUGGGUGGGGAGGUGGUGGGGGCCGGCGUCCCCUGCGUGUGUGUGUGUGUGUGUGUGUGUGGAUGUAUUGACCUGUGUUUCCCAAGACAGCAGGUGCCACGGCCCGCCCCGCCUGCCAGCCCGAAUUCCCGUUCUCCUGUGUCUACUAACAAGGACAUGGGGGUGGGCGGUGACCUCCGCAUCCCUCAGAGCUCAGAGGGUCCUCGCUGCCACCGGUCCCCCCCUAGCCCGUCAUCAGCCGGUGGCAGCUCCAUCUUCCAUUCCUGGUUUUAGGGCAGAAUCCAUGGAGACUGCUUCCAGAAGGCAUCUGGCUCUGAGUUAUAAAUUACUUCCCUGGUCCUGACAGUCACCUGGGGUCCCCCCUCUCCCUGGUUCCACCUUUCUGAGGAGGAGCCUGGAGUCAGGGCUGGGUUUUGGAUUAACCCAUCCUUCCUAGUUAACACCUUUUUGUUUUUAUUUUAUUUUAUUUUUGUUUGUUUUCUCCGUGUGUGUGUUUUCCUAAUUUAUUUACCUCUGUUUCCCCUUUUUCCUUUUUUUUUUUAAUUAAAGAGCAAAGCUUUUUAUUACUUUGUAAUUUAAAAAACUGAAAAAAAAAAAACUGAAGAACUUUGGGGGGAAUUUUGUACUUUUUUCCUGUGUAAAUAUUGGACUUUUUUGAGCUUUAUCGUGGUUGUUAAUUUGAAGUAAUAAAGUAGAAAAGAUAAAGUGA